GGGCAAAAAAAUCAAGGUAUUUGGUCCCGGAACAAAGCUUAUCAUUACAGAUAAACAACUUGAUGCAGAUGUUUCCCCCAAGCCCACUAUUUUUCUUCCUUCAAUUGCUGAAACAAAGCUCCAGAAGGCUGGAACAUACCUUUGUCUUCUUGAGAAAUUUUUCCCUGAUGUUAUUAAGAUACAUUGGCAAGAAAAGAAGAGCAACACGAUUCUGGGAUCCCAGGAGGGGAACACCAUGAAGACUAACGACACAUACAUGAAAUUUAGCUGGUUAACGGUGCCAGAAAAGUCACUGGACAAAGAACACAGAUGUAUCGUCAGACAUGAGAAUAAUAAAAACGGAGUUGAUCAAGAAAUUAUCUUUCCUCCAAUAAAGACAGAUGUCAUCACAAUGGAUCCCAAAGACAAUUGUUCAAAAGAUGCAAAUGAUACACUACUGCUGCAGCUCACAAACACCUCUGCAUAUUACAUGUACCUCCUCCUGCUCCUCAAGAGUGUGGUCUAUUUUGCCAUCAUCACCUGCUGUCUGCUUAGAAGAACGGCUUUCUGCUGCAAUGGAGAGAAAUCAUAACAGACGGUGGCACAAGGAGGCCAUCUUUUCCUCAUCGGUUAUUGUCCCUAGAAGCGUCUUCUGAGGAUCUAGUUGGGCUUUCUUUCUGGGUUUGGGCCAUUUCAGUUCUCAUGUGUGUACUAUUCUAUCAUUAUUGUAUAACGGUUUUCAAACCAGUGGGCACACAGAGAACCUCACUCUGUAAUAACAAUGAGGAAUAGCCACGGCGAUCUCCAGCACCAAUCUCUCCAUGUUUUCCACAGCUCCUCCAGCCAACCCAAAUAGCGCCUGCUAUAGUGUAGACAUCCUGCGGCUUCUAGCCUUGUCCCUCUCUUAGUGUUCUUUAAUCAGAUAACUGCCUGGAAGCCUUUCAUUUUACACGCCCUGAAGCAGUCUUCUUUGCUAGUUGAAUUAUGUGGUGUGUUUUUCCGUAAUAAGCAAAAUAAAUUUAAAAAAAUGAAAAGUU